AGAGCAAAGAGGCAAUCUGAAGAGAAAAGCAUAGGAAAGGAAACAGUGGUAAUAGGAAUUGGGGUAAAAUGAGGAUCCUUCCCCACAAACAUUGCUAUUAUUCAGCUCAUUUCAAAGGAUUCCGCUGCUGCCAUUUGUGAGAGCCGCUGGAGGCUGAGUGAAAGUCAUUUUGAAAGACUGAUCCAAAGAAGAAUGGAGGCCAGAGUGGAGCGUGCUGUGCAGAAAAGGCAAGUCUUAUUUCUUUGUGUAUUUCUGGGAAUGUCUUGGGCUGGCGCCGAACCGCUUCGGUAUUUUGUGGCGGAGGAAACCGAGAGAGGCACCUUUCUUACCAACUUGGCAAAAGACCUAGGGUUAGGGGUAGGGGAACUGAGAGCCCGGGGAACUAGAAUUGUUUCAGACCAGAACAUGCAAAUUUUACUGCUCAGUUCGCUUACUGGUGAUCUACUUCUAAAUGAGAAAUUGGACCGAGAGGAACUGUGUGGCCCCAGAGAGCCCUGUGUGCUGCCUUUCCAGUUGUUAUUGGAAAAACCUUUUCAGAUUUUCCGUGCUGAACUAUGGGUCAGAGACAUCAAUGAUCACGCUCCAGUAUUUCUAGACAGAGAGAUUUCCUUGAAAAUAUUAGAAAGUACCACUCCAGGGGCGGCAUUUCUCCUAGAGAGUGCACAGGAUUCAGAUGUUGGAACCAACAGCCUGAGUAACUACACCAUCAGCCCCAAUGCCUAUUUCCAUAUUAAUGUCCAUGAUAGCGGGGAGGGGAAUAUCUAUCCCGAAUUGGUGCUGAAUCAAGUGCUGGAUCGGGAAGAGAUACCAGAGUUCAGUUUAACCCUCACCGCUUUAGACGGCGGCUCUCCUCCAAGAUCAGGGACCGCCCUCGUGCGCAUUCUGGUUCUAGACGUAAAUGACAACGCCCCUGAUUUUGUGCGGUCGCUCUACAAGGUGCAGGUGCCCGAAAAUAGCCCCGUUGGUUCCAUGGUUGUCUCCGUGUCAGCCAGAGAUUUAGAUACCGGAAGUAAUGGGGAAAUAGCCUAUGCAUUUUCUUACGCCACUGAAAGAAUUCUCAAAACGUUUCAAAUCAAUCCAACAUCUGGCAGUCUUCAUCUUAAAGCGCAAUUGGACUAUGAGGCAAUUCAAACUUACACAUUAACUAUUCAGGCCAAAGACGGCGGCGGGCUUUCUGGAAAAUGCACUGUAGUGGUUGAUGUAACAGAUAUAAACGAUAAUCGACCCGAGCUGCUCCUGUCUUCACUUACUAGCCCAAUUGCAGAAAACUCACCCGAGACAGUCGUGGCUGUUUUUAGGAUUAGAGACAGAGAUUCCGGGAACAAUGGAAAGACAGUGUGCUCCAUCCAGGACGAUGUCCCCUUCAUCCUGAAGCCAUCUGUCGAAAACUUCUAUACUCUGGUAACAGAGAAACCUUUGGAUCGAGAGAGGAACACUGAGUACAACAUCACCAUCACCGUCACCGACUUGGGGACACCCAGGCUGAAAACCGAGCACAACAUAACCGUGCUGGUCUCCGACGUCAAUGACAACGCUCCCGCCUUCACCCAAACCUCCUACACCCUGUUUGUCCGUGAGAACAACAGCCCCGCCCUGCCCAUCGGCAGUGUCAGCGCCACAGACAGAGACUCGGGCACCAACGCCCAGGUCAUCUACUCCCUGCUGCCGUCCCAGGACCCGCACCUGCCCCUCGCCUCCCUGGUCUCCAUCAACGCGGACAACGGCCACCUGUUUGCCCUCAGGUCCCUGGACUACGAGGCCCUGCAGGCGUUCGAGUUCCGCGUGGGCGCCACAGACCGCGGCUCCCCCGCGCUGAGCAGCGAGGCGCUGGUGCGCGUGCUGGUGCUGGACGCCAACGACAACUCGCCCUUCGUGCUGUACCCGCUGCAGAACAGCUCCGCGCCCUGCACCGAGCCGUUGCCCCGGGCGGCCGAGCCGGGCUACCUGGUGACCAAGGUGGUGGCGGUGGACGGCGACUCGGGCCAGAACGCCUGGCUGUCGUACCAGCUGCUCAAGGCCACGGAGCCCGGGCUAUUCGGCGUGUGGGCGCACAAUGGCGAGGUGCGUACCGCCAGGCUGCUGAGCGAGCGCGACGCAGCCAAGCAGAGGCUGGUGGUGCUGGUCAAGGACAAUGGCGAGCCUCCGCGCUCGGCCACCGCCACGCUGCACGUGCUCCUGGUGGACGGCUUCUCCCAGCCCUACCUGCGGCUCCCGGAGGCGGCCCCGGACCAGGCCAACUCGCUCACCGUCUACCUGGUGGUGGCGUUGGCCUCGGUGUCUUCGCUCUUCCUCCUCUCGGUGCUCCUGUUCGUGGCGGUGCGGCUGUGCAGGAGGAGCAGGGCGGCCCCGGUGGGUCGCUGCUCGGUGCCUGAGGGCCCCUUUCCACGACAUCUGGUGGACUUGAGCGGCACCGGGACCCUAUCCCAGAGCUACCAGUAUGAGGUGUGCCUGACUGGAGGCUCCGGGACAAAUGAGUUCAAGUUUCUGAAACCAAUUAUCCCCAACCUGCUACCCCAGAGCACAGGCAGGGAAGUGGAAGAAAAUCGCCCAUUUCAGAAUAAUUUGGGUUUCUGAUAAAGAAUGUAAACUAAAUCCGCGUCUGUGAAUACGUUUCUGAUUAGGAACUUAUUGCGAGGUUCCCUUAAGGGAGUGUCUUUACAUCAUUUCAAAUAUGUACUCUUGAAGUCAAGCAAUAAAUUUCUAUACAUAAAAUAGGAUCCUGAUUUAGUAUCAAGAACCCUUCACAAAGCAUGAAAUGUAUAUGUGUAAUGUUUUAUGUCAAACAAUUAUGCUUAAUAUACAGUCUAUUAAAUGUAAGUCUUGUUUGAGAUAUUUUAAAUUGCUUUCCAUUGUUUUCAAUCUCUACUGAGACUUCCUGAGUUGAUUAGAAAGCUGUAUGAGUGUACCUACCCUAGUCUCAGAAGCAUAGACUGUAGAGUAUCUUUUUAAGCAUUUUUAAAAAAUGCUUUUAAUGCAUCAUACACUAUUUUAACACUUUUAAUCUGAGAAGAAGCAUAUGAGGCAUGGUAUUUUAGGAAUGAACAAAUAGAUGGUCUUAGAGAUUCAGUAAGUUCACUAAGUUCCACUAACUAAUAAGUGACAAAACUGAGCAUCCAUCCCAGAUCUGUCUGACUCUGGGUCAGUGACCCUGCUCCGAUUCCAUACUGUUUUCUGUCAUUAGAUAUCACCUGGCAAGUUUCUGCCUAAUUAAGGAGAAGUCUUUUAUCAUAUUUAUACUGCUGUCCAAUCUUUUCUAUAUUUAGAAAUAAUAAUGUACAUAUUUAUCUAUGGUUUUAUUUUCUUAUACACCAAAAGUCCUGCUUUUCUGGGUCAAUUUUCAACUAUUAUUACUAAUGCUCUGAUCUGUCCAAACUCAAGCGGAAAACAAAAUUGAAAGGGCAACCUGUGCCUUCUCCUUUCUUCAGAACAUAUGACUUUCAUUUCCCAGAAAAAAGAUUAAUGGUCCUGAGUAGGAAUAUUACAUAAUUUUGAUUGCAUCAUUAGUUAAUUAUUUUCUUCAUAUUGUAGAUUUUCUGCAGUCACCCAUACUUAACAUUUGUAAUACAUUUUCCUGAUUUGAAAGUUUGUUUUUAAAAGUUUUCUAUUAAUUAUAGUGCACUAUUGAAUCAGGAAAAUUUAAGAAAAAGAAUAGUUAGUUUUAAAUGCAUAAUAUCAAAGAGAAUCAUAGAUGAUCAUUAAAUUUUUAGAAAUUCUCGGAAGUUAAGGAGAAGCACUGUUUU